AGUGAGACUGUAGGGUGGGCGGUGCGAGCGGCGGUUAGCUCCCAGUUCGGCCUCUGAGGAAAACGGGCGUUCGCCUGCGGUUGGUCCGACUGUUAGCAACAUGAGCGGCCUGGAUGGGGUCAAGAGGACCACUCCCCUCCAAACCCACAGCAUCAUUAUUUCUGACCAAGUCCCGAGCGACCAGGACGCACACCAGUACCUGAGGCUCCGCGACCAAAGCGAGGCGACACAGGUGAUGGCGGAGCCGGGUGAGGGAGGCUCGGAGACCGUCGCGCUCCCGCCUCCACCGCCUUCAGAGGAGGGGGGCGUACCCCAGGAUGCCGCGGGCCGUGGCGGUACUCCCCAGAUCCGAGUUGUUGGGGGUCGCGGUCAUGUGGCGAUCAAAGCCGGGCAGGAAGAGGGCCAGCCUCCCGCCGAAGGCCUGGCAGCCGCUUCUGUGGUGAUGGCAGCCGACCGCAGCCUGAAAAAGGGCGUUCAGGGUGGAGAGAAGGCCCUAGAAAUCUGUGGCGCCCAGAGAUCCGCGUCUGAGCUGACGGCGGGGGCGGAGGCUGAGGCGGAGGAGGUGAAGACAGGAAAGUGCGCCACCGUCUCAGCAGCCGUGGCUGAGAGGGAGAGCGCUGAGGUGGUGAAGGAAGGCCUGGCGGAGAAGGAGGUAAUGGAGGAGCAGAUGGAGGUAGAGGAGCAGCCGCCAGAAGGUGAAGAAAUAGAAGUGGCGGAGGAGGAUAGAUUGGAGGAGGAGGCGAGGGAGGAAGAAGGGCCCUGGCCUUUGCAUGAGGCUCUCCGCAUGGACCCUCUGGAGGCCAUCCAGCUGGAACUGGACACUGUGAAUGCUCAGGCCGACAGGGCCUUCCAACAGCUGGAGCACAAGUUUGGGCGGAUGCGUCGACACUACCUGGAGCGGAGGAACUACAUCAUUCAGAAUAUCCCGGGCUUCUGGAUGACUGCUUUUCGAAACCACCCCCAGUUGUCCGCCAUGAUUAGGGGCCAAGAUGCAGAGAUGUUAAGGUACAUAACCAAUUUAGAGGUGAAGGAACUCAGACACCCUAGAACCGGUUGCAAGUUCAAGUUCUUCUUUAGAAGAAACCCCUACUUCAGAAACAAGCUGAUUGUCAAGGAAUAUGAGGUAAGAUCCUCCGGCCGAGUGGUGUCUCUUUCUACUCCAAUUAUAUGGCGCAGGGGGCAUGAACCCCAGUCCUUCAUUCGCAGAAACCAAGACCUCAUCUGCAGCUUCUUCACUUGGUUUUCAGACCACAGCCUUCCAGAGUCCGACAAAAUUGCUGAGAUUAUUAAAGAGGAUCUGUGGCCAAAUCCACUGCAAUACUACCUGUUGCGUGAAGGAGUCCGUAGAGCCCGACGUCGCCCGCUAAGGGAGCCUGUAGAGAUCCCCAGGCCCUUUGGGUUCCAGUCUGGUUAACAUUUGCCCUUGGGAAUACUCCUGCACAAGGUCUCCUACCACCUUCUGCUGGACCUGUGCUUGGGCAUCAGCAAUGAGUAUGCCUUCUAUUGUGCUUUGUUUUUGCUGACUUUUCUGCACCCUGUUUCCUUUGGAUAUUCAGUUCUCUCAACCUCAAGAUUGAGACGGUGGUGGGUAUGCUUCUCCACUUCCAUAUGACCUUCAUGCUGUUCUGGAAUAUCACAUGCUACGAGGUCAUCCUUCACACUACUUGUAAGCCAAGCAAAUGAUACUGUAGAUUGUACUGCCUUUAUCUGCACUGCUUGGACCCUGUUUAUUCCCAGGGCCUCUGAACUGGUUGCUGUCACUUGGAUUUCUAGCUUUGGGAGCCUGUUCCACCUACUCAGCUCUGCAUUGAGCAGUAUGGGCACAUGCCCUGUGGACAGUUACUGGACGUUAAUGAACUCAGAGGAGAAAAGCAGUGAGCCACUUGUUCUGUGUGAUUUAUGGUACUUCAUUGCUCUUCCUUCACCUCUAGUCACUUUCUAUUGCUACCUGCCCUACAUUGGCUCCUGCCAAGGUCCCUCUCUCUCCCUGUUUUCCUUUUUUUUUUUUUUUUUUUUUUUUUUGAGACGGAGGACGGAGUCUUGCUCUGUCGCCCAGGUUGGAGUGCAGUGGCGCGAUCUCGGCUCACUGCAACCUCCACCUCCCGGGUUCAAGCGAUUCUCCUGCCUCAGCCUCCCGAGUAGCUGGGACUACAGGCGCGCGCCGCCACGCCCGGCUAAUUUUUAUAUUUUUAGUAGAGACGGGGUUUCACCAUGCUGGCCAGGCUGGUCUCGAACCCCGAUCUCGUGAUCCGCCCUCCUUAGCCUCCCAAUCCUCUCUUAAAAAAGUGAUAGCUCAGAAACAUUUGUAAAAGCAAGGUUUUUAUUUCAUUUUGGCUCUGUCAUUUUCAGAGGCAAAGAAGUUGGCCUGUAAAAUAGAGUGCUAGAGCUCUUACGCCCCUCCCCUUCUUCCCAACUUCCUACUUCCUAGCCCUUUUAUCAACUCCUAGAAUAGUUAAAGAGAGACACAUCUAGAUGGGAUGAAAGGUGCCCUAAGCAGGAGAAACUGAACAAAAGGCUAGAGGCAUGGGCCAGGUAAAAAUUGGGCCUAGAGUGAAGACUGUGCUGUCGUUAAGAGCUUUCGAGGAAGGAGUACUUACUCCCCAAUGAUGAUGAAUGGAAAAAUACUUUUCAGGGAGAAUUGAAGGGGUUAAAGUGUUAAAUAUGUUGCCUAGACAAGGGUUCUUUAAAGAAAGACAGCGCAACUUUGAAUGCUUUCUUACUUGUUUUGUGACCUAAUUUAUGUGGAAGAUUGUUAUUUCAUUAGGAUUUAGUAAAAUUUUUUUUUCUGAUUCUAAACUUAUUGUGAAAAUUGAGCUGUACAGAUAUUCUUUUGAUUUCAAUUGGGAACAUUUGGAAGAACAACAGUCUUACUUGCCUGUACAAUAUAGAGACAUAUGAAUAGUCAUAACAGUUUUCAACUUGUUCUUGUUUCUGUUAAACUAUAUUCCUAGAAACAUAGUUUGAACAACUUGGUCUUUGUUAGGCUUGUCAAAUUGCCUUCAUGGAAAAAUAAUCUACAAAAGUAUGGUUUAAUUGAUUGUCUUACAUGAUAAUUUUCCCUGGUAACAACUUAGUAAGUGAUAUAUCUUUUUUCCUAAAUUGCUUAAAUACUGUGAAAUUGCUCUGACAAAUUGGAAGUGUACCAUUGGCAUAUUUGUCUUCCUUUUUAUGCAUGAUGGUAAAAUAAAAGCAUGUUGUUCUGCUAGAUUUCUUAUUUUUCACCUUACCCAUAAAUGUAAUGCUUGAAUGAAGUUGUUCAUAUUAAUUAAAAAUUAUGGAAUCAUUAAAGUCCUUUAAUCCAUUAAAGUUCUUAAUGGAUUAAAAUCAUUAAAGUUCUUAAUGGAUUAAAAUCAUUAAAGUCCUUAAAUUGAUGUUAACUAAAAAUUACAGAAUCAUUAAAGUCCUUAAAUGGACACAAUAGACAUUAUCCCAAAGAGAAGAAAGCAGGGCACGGUAUGUUUGGUACCUUCCAAGGUAGUUUGCCUUAAAACGUUAGCAGUUGCAACUGCUUACUCAAUCACUUUUUUCCAUGUAGUUUAUGCAGCACAACCUCCCCUUCAGUUGCUCAAAUCCUCCAUUUCUGUCUCCAUAAAUUAUAUUCUCAGGUUAUUCAGGCUCUUCUUUUUAUUAACUUGUAUGCAGGGAGUACCUAUCAUAUGUGAUGUACUCCUCUAUUUUCAUACUUUCUCAUCUGUAAAAACUUCCUUUUUUUCUUUAAACUUCCUCACUGUUCUCUUCUGUCAAAUCCUUCAAGGCCUGCCCUUGGUAAUUCCUCUGCCAAAGUCUUUCUGUUCCCCAUAGAGGAGAUAAAUGUUUCUUUAUGCACUUAGUGUACUUUGGAGGGACCUCUGUUCUAGAAAAUUAACAUAAUUAUUCAUUACAGUGAAUUCCACAAAUAGAGAAAAAGAGUAAGAAGAUAAAGUCCAUUCCCUUCUUUGGGGAACUGGGGAAGGACUGAUAAGCAAACAAAGAAUUAACAGAGUGAUACAGUAAAAUAAAAUACAGAGAUUAUAUUUUCAUGUUUUUCCCAUGUUCACUCUUUUCCUCUCAGUAGUUUGGAAACUUUGUGAAAGUGGAGAUGCAGUGCAUUUUACAUGGUUCAUUGCAUCUAGCAUUUUUUUUUUUUUUUUUUGAGAUAGAGUCCCACUCUUGCCCAGGCUGGAGCGCAAGUGGCGCGAUCUCGGCUCACUGCAACUUCCGCCUCCCGGUUUCAAGCAGUUCUCCAGCAUCAGCCUCCCGAGUAGCUGGGACUACAGGCACGUGCUACCACGCCCGGCUAAUUUUUUGUAUUUUUAGUAGAGAUGGGGUUUCACCAUGUUAGCCAGGAUGGUCUCCAUCUCCUGACCUCGUGAUCAGCCCACCUCAGCCUCCCAAAGUGCUGGGAUUACAGGCGUGAGCCACCGCACCCAGCCCAUCUAGCAUAAUGUUUUGCAUAGUUGUCAGCAGAUAAAUAUUGAAUGACAAAACUCAGAUGGAGGAAAAAGAACAAAAUAACCUAGUUCUCAGAAAGAUUUAAUGAGCAAAUGGGAAAAUGUCAAAAAGAUUUGCAAUGCCAUUCCUAAAUAACUAUUUCCCCUUUUAGUCAUUAGAAAACGUCUAAACACUUUCAACAUUAAAUCUUUCACUUGCAUUUUAACAGAGCACUACUUAAUUUUGGGUUACCUUUUAUAUACUUUGUACAUUUUAAGGUGAUUAUACUGGAGAUAGAAGGGGGUUAGACUCUAGAUGUGUGUUGUCCAAUACAGUAACUUUUAGCCACCAGUGGCUAUUGAGCACUUGAAAUGUGGCUAGUCUGAAUUGAGAUCUAUAAAUAUAAAAUUCACACUGGAUUUUGAAGACUCAGUAUGGAAAGAAAAAUGUUAAAAUAUCUCAAUUUUUUUCAUAUUGAUUGCAUGUUGAAAUAUUUUUGACAUUGUGUUAAAAUAUAUUGAAAAAUUAAUUAUCCUCAUUUUGCCAUUGUUUAAUGUGGCUACUAGUAAAUCUAAAAUUACAUAGGACAGCAUGUCUCGACUUCCUGAGGAAUAUCUGAAAGCAUAUAAAAUAUCUGUAAAAAUUAAACAUGUUAAUACUUUC